AGCCUCCCAGAGCCUGCAGCCCGGCCAUGGCCCAGUCGCCUCCUCCGCAGAGCCUCCUCGGCCACGACCACUGGAUCUUCGCCCAGGGCUGGGGCUGGGCCGGCCACUGGGACUCCACGUCCCCGGCCUCCUCCUCCGAUUCGUCGGGUUCGUGCCCCUGCGACGGCGCCCGCGGACUCCCGCAGCCACAGCCUCCGAGCUGCAGCUCCCGAGCCGCAGAGGCAGCCGCGACGACGCCCAGACGAGCGCGCACCGGACCAGCGGGCGGACAGCGGCAGAGCGCCAGCGAGCGGGAGAAACUGCGCAUGCGCACGCUGGCCCGCGCCCUGCACGAGUUGCGCCGCUUUCUGCCUCCCUCCUUGGCGCCGGCCGGCCAGAGCCUGACCAAGAUCGAGACGCUGCGCCUGGCCAUCCGCUACAUCGGCCACCUAUCGGCCGUGCUGGGUCUCAGCGAGGAGAGUCUGCAGUGCCGGCGCAGGCAGCGCGGGGACGCGGGGUCCCCUUGGGGCUGCCCGCUGUGCCCCGACCGUGGCCCCGCAGAGGCGCAGACGCAGGCGGAGGGGCAGGGGCAAGGGCAGGGGCAGGGGCAGGGGCAAGGGCAGGGGCAAGGACAGGGGCAAGGACAGGGGCAAGGGCAGGGGCGCAGGCCGGGCCUGGUCUCCGCCGUCCUCGCCGAGGCGUCCUGGGGAUCCCCGUCCGCCUGCCCCGGAGCCCAAGCCGCACCCGAGCGCCUGGGGAGGGGGGUCCACGACACGGAUCCCUGGGCAACACCCCCUUACUGCCCCAAGAUACAGUCGCCCCCGUAUUCGUCCCAAGGGACAACCUCCGACGCGUCUCUUUGGACGCCACCCCAAGGCUGUCCCUGGACGCAGUCGUCCCCAGAGCCCCGGAACCCACCAGUGCCCUGGACGGCGGCCCCAGCAACUUUGGAGCUGGCCGCAGUGUACCAGGGUCUCUCUGUGUCUCCAGAGCCCUGUCUGUCGCUGGGAGCUCCAUCUCUCCUGCCCCACCCAUCAUGCCAGAGACUGCAGCCUCAGACCCCCGGGAGGUGCUGGAGCCACAGUGCAGAGGUGGUGCCCAACUCAGAGGACCAGGGACCGGGCGCCGCCUUCCAGCUCAGUGAAGCAAGCCCUCCCCAGAGCUCAGGCCUGCGGUUCAGUGGCUGCCCUGAACUUUGGCAAGAAGAUCUGGAGGGGGCCCGCCUGGGCAUCUUCUACUAAAUGGCCUCGGCUUCCCUCUUUCCAUCCAGGAAUCAGUCCUGUAGCUUGGGUGCCUCCUUAUUUGUUAAUUAGUGGCUUUUCAUGUUCUCCUUUAGCCAAGGCUCCCUUUUUCCAAGUGAUGUCUUUCAGGGAAGCAGUGUUUGAAAUAGAUAGCGGGUACCUUCCCUGGAUGGAGUCAGGGCGGGGGCACUGUCCUCCACUGCUAGACACCCCCAGAAUGCCUGGCGCUCUGCAGAGCACAGUCUGAGCUGCUCUAAGAAGGGGUCUCCUUUACCCUAAAGGCAGCUGGGCAGGGACAGGUGGGAGAAUGGGUGUAGGAGGCAGGCCCCAGGCUCUGCUUCUUGGUGACAGUUGGCCAGAGCCCUGUAUGCUUUGAUUUUUUUGUACUUAAAAAGAAAAAACACACACACACAACAAAAA